GUUCCCCAAACACAGUGAGUGAGGACGGACCUCAGGCUGUCUCUUCGGGUCACCGCUGUGAAAACAAGGCAGGUACAGCACCAGGGCACACACUCGCCCCCAGGGGAGGCUCCCCCAGAUCCCAGGCCUCUAGGCCCCACAUCAACAGUGCACUGCACGUUGAGGACAAGGCCAUCUCGGACUGCAGACCCUCACGGCCUUCCCACACUUUGUCCUCACUUGCAACAGGGGCUUCCGGUGGGCCUCCCGUUUCUAAAGCACCCACUAUGGACGCACAGCAGGACAGACCCAAGUCCCAAGACUGCCUGGGCCUAGUGGCCCCCCUAGCAUCUGCUGCAGAGGUCCCCUCUACAGCUCCCGUGUCUGGGAAGAAGCACAGACCACCAGGACCCCUGUUCUCCUCCUCAGAUCCCCUUCCUGCCACCUCUUCCCACUCCCGGGACUCAGCCCAGGUCACCUCGCUGAUUCCUGCCACCUUCACAGCUGCAAGCAGGGAUGCCGGCAUGAGAAGAACAAGGCCUGGCACCUCGGCUCCUGCAGCUGCCGCAGCAGCCCCUCCCCCCUCCACAUUGAACCCCACGUCGGGGUCGCUACUCAAUGCAGUGGAUGGAGGCCCCGCACAUUUCUUGGGCUCAGCCACAGCUGCAGCACGUGCCCAGAGGUCAGAAGUGAGAUAUAACCAGAGAUCCCAGACCUCCCGGACCAGAUCGUGCCUCAAACGAAAUGCCAGCUCCAGCUCCCACAGCUCUACGGAAGGCCUCCACGAAGUAAAGCGGAGGAGGGGGCCAGCCUCAUCCCACUGCCAGCUGGCCCACAGUUCCUCAGUGAGUGAGGACGGACCUCAGGCUGUCUCUUCGGGUCACCGCUGUGAAAACAAGGCAGGUACAGCACCAGGGCAGACACUCGCCCCCAGGGGUGGCUCCCCCAGAUCCCAGGCCUCUAGGCCCCGCAUCAACACUGCACUGCACGUUGAGGACAAGGCCAUCUCGGACUGCAGACCCUCACGGCCUUCCCACACUUUGUCCUCACUUGCAACAGGGGCUUCCGGUGGGCCUCCCGUUUCUAAAGCACCCACUAUGGAUGCACAGCAGGACAGACCCAAGUCCCAAGACUGCCUGGUCCUACUGGCCCCCCUAGCAUCUGCUGCAGAGGUCCCCUCUACAGCUCCCGUGUCUGGGAAGAAGCACAGACCACCAGGACCCCUGUUCUCCUCCUCAGAUCCCCUUCCUGCCACCUCUUCCCACUCCCGGGACUCAGCCCAGGUCACCUCGCUGAUUCCCGCGCCCUUCACAGCUGCAAGCAGCGAUGCCGGCAUGAGAAGAACAAGGCCUGGCACCUCGGCUCCUGCAGCUGCAGCAGCAGCCCCUCCCCCCUCCACAUUGCACCCCACGUCGGGGUCACUACUCAAUGCAGUGGAUGGAGGCCCCUCACAUUUCUUGGCCUCAGCCACAGCUGCAGCACGUGUCCAGAGGUCAGAAGUGAGAUAUAACCAGAGAUCCCAGACCUCCCGGACCAGAUCCUGCCUCCAAGGAAAUGCCAGCUCCAGCUCCCACAGCUCUACGGAAGGCCUCCCGCAACUAAAGCGGAGGAGGGGGCCAGCCUCAUCCCACUGCCAGCUGGCCCACAGUUCCUCAAACACAGUGAGUGAGGACGGACCUCAGGCUGUCUCUUCGGGUCACACCCGCUGUGAGAAGAAGGCAGGUACAGCACCAGGGCAGACACUUGCCCCCAGGGGUGGCUCCCCCAGAUCCCAGGCCUCUAGGCCCCGCAUCAACACUGCACUGCACGUUGAGGACAAGGCCAUCUCGGACUGCAGACCCUCACGGCCUUCCCACACUUUGUCCUCACUUGCAACAGGGGCUUCGGGUGGGCCUCCCGUUUCUAAAGCACCCACUAUGGAUGCACAGCAGGACAGACCCAAGUCCCAAGACUGCCUGGGCCUACUGGCCCCCCUAGCAUCUGCUGCAGAGGUCUCCUCUACAGCUCCCGUGUCUGGGAAGAAGCACAGACCACCAGGACCCCUGUUCUCCUCCUCAGAUCCCCUUCCUGCCACCUCUUCCCACUCCGGGGACUCAGCCCAGGACACCUCGCUGAUUCCUGCCCCCUUCACACCUGCAAGCAGGGAUGCCGGCAUCAGAAGAAUGUUUCGUGUUCGAAAUUGUUUGAGGGGUUUGGGUUUAUUUUUGUUGGUUUUUUCUUUUUUUUUUUUGCUUACGUGGGCAUCCUUCAGCUUUUAAUAAUCUGAAAAAUUCUAUUUACCCAUUGUCAAUGUGUAUAAAUUAAUCUCAGUCAAUUUUAUACAAUAAAAGGUGAACUUUUAUCCAUCAAACAAUAAUUUAACAAAAAAUGUACCGGAAGAAGAAUGUUCAUUACAAAUAUAGGAAACAUAAAUAUUACCAAAUAUUGGCAAGCACUAAAAUGUUCAGAAAUAUAAGUCUAUUACAGUUAUAGCUCUCUCAAGCAAAAAAACAGCAGAGAAAAACUUAGUUUACCUGAGGGGCUAUUUAUUUACUUAGGGAUUUGUUAAAAGGUCAAAUGGGGUCACACAGAAUACUAAGAAGAGCUGUUCAUCCAGGCCUCACUAAGAACUCUUCUUCAUGCAGUAGCUAUAUGGUAAUAUGACAACUGCUCCUACGACCCAAAGAGGAACUACAGCAACUACUCUUUAGCAUCUGUUGCUCCCAACUCUGCUUUGCAAUUAUAUGACUCAAGCAUUCUGGCUCCGUUAACUAUUACUGCUGUUACUCCCAAGUAAAUUCCCUCUAAAAAAUAAAAAUUUUUAAAGCUGUAA